GGAAGAACUUGUUCUGUGGGUGUCUCAUCAGUCUCUCUUCUGAGGGAAAUAUUAGCUCAGCCUGCAGGCUGAUCAUCAUAAAAUAUGAAGAAAAGGAGUUUGCCUGCAUCAUCUCAAAAGCAGUGAUUUCAUGAAUGCGUCAGUUUCCAUUUAUGUCAACAUCAUCGCUUUGUCUCUUAUCUCCUGAUUUCUUGUCCUCCAGCAAGUGCAACUGUUAGAAUUCUCCAAGUCAGAAGAUCUGACUCUGAAAAGUACCCUAAGUUUGUUUUGCUAUGGGGUUGUUCAAUGUCACUCACCCUGCAUUCUUCCUCCUGACUGGUAUCCCUGGUCUGGAGAGCUCUCACUCCUGGCUGUCAGGGCCCCUCUGCGUGAUGUAUGCUGUGGCCCUUGGGGGAAAUACAGUGAUCCUGCAGGCUGUGCGAGUGGAGCCCAGCCUCCAUGAGCCCAUGUACUACUUCCUGUCCAUGUUGUCCUUCAGUGAUGUGGCCAUAUCCAUGGCCACACUGCCCACUGUACUCCGAACCUUCUGCCUCAAUGCCCGCAACAUCACUUUUGAUGCCUGUCUAAUUCAGAUGUUUCUUAUUCACUUCUUCUCCAUGAUGGAAUCAGGUAUUCUGCUGGCCAUGAGUUUUGACCGCUAUGUGGCCAUUUGUGACCCCUUGCGCUAUGCAACUGUGCUCACCACUGAAGUCAUUGCUGCAAUGGGUUUAGGUGCAGCUGCUCGAAGCUUCAUCACCCUUUUCCCUCUUCCCUUUCUUAUUAAGAGGCUGCCUAUCUGCAGAUCCAAUGUUCUUUCUCACUCCUACUGCCUGCACCCAGACAUGAUGAGGCUUGCCUGUGCUGAUAUCAGUAUCAACAGCAUCUAUGGACUCUUUGUUCUUGUAUCCACCUUUGGCAUGGACCUGUUUUUUAUCUUCCUCUCCUAUGUGCUCAUUCUGCGUUCUGUCAUGGCCACUGCUUCCCGUGAGGAACGCCUCAAAGCUCUCAACACAUGUGUGUCACAUAUCCUGGCUGUACUUGCAUUUUAUGUGCCAAUGAUUGGGGUCUCCACAGUGCACCGCUUUGGGAAGCAUGUCCCAUGCUACAUACAUGUCCUCAUGUCAAAUGUGUACCUAUUUGUGCCUCCUGUGCUCAACCCUCUCAUUUAUAGCGCCAAGACAAAGGAAAUCCGCCGAGCCAUUUUCCGCAUGUUUCACCACAUCAAAAUAUGACUUUCACACUUGGCUUUAGAAUCUGUUAUUUUGGCCAUAGGCUCUCAUCAGUAGCAUCGUCAUCAUCAUCAUCAAAGUAUAAGAUAGAUUGUGUGCUGCGGGAAAAGUAGGCCAGGAGAUGGUGAUGCAAAACUUAUAACACAAAACAAGGAGUUCCAAAUGAAUAGUACAUUCACUAAAUACCAACAGUAUUCUUAGAAAGAUAAAUAUUGGGGGCAAUUGAGUAAUUAGACAAGUUUUACAGAGGAAGACUAAUUUAAGCUAGGAAUUAUUUUCUAUAAUAAUGAAUAUUACUAAUAUAAUAAUUAACAAACUUAGUCCUAAAAUGUAUCAAGUACUAUUAUAAAUUAUUUGUGUGUAUUAAUUCACUUAAUAUUCAUACAAAUCCUCUAAGACACAGAGAAUUAAGUUAAUUCUUCAGCCUAACACAGAUAAUAUGUGGUCCAGUUGACAUUCAACACUAAUCUCUCUCUAGUGUCAGUGCAGCACCCAACCGGUAUAAAUAUGGCCUGACGGUCAAAUUGGCAUCAUUUAACAUUACCAUUGCUGCCUUUGCUUUCCCCACCACUGUCAUUCUCAAACACUCAUACAUUGCUUUAACUUCACAAAGUGAAAUCAGCUUAACUAUUAGAACUCACCAUAAAAUGUAUGAACAAAUGUGAUCCAGGUAAACUGAUAGAUAUUGCCAUUUAGGAAAAUCUCCAGAUUCUUCUUUACUUCUUUUAUCUGCCCACCACUCAAUCCUUACCAACAGAAAACAAUGUUCAAUAUCUGAAAUAUCUGACUCAUAGAAUUUUGGGGGAAAGGGGGAAUUGUGGUAGGGGCACAAUUUCUAUUUCUCUUUCCUUCUUGAGAUUUUAACUGUCUUCCACAAAAUGACAUGUUAAGAGAUGUUAGAAAUUAAGUCAGUCUAGGAUUUCCAGUUGCAAAAAAAAAAAGCCUAGGAUAGACAGACUAGAGCACUUAUGGUUUAGAUACCAGAAAAUAAUUCUUUCAGACCUUCUCAUACGCUUCCCUUGAUACCAGAGGUAGGAUAUAGUAAGAAAUUCCUUGGUGCUAAUUUUGGUGCUGUCAUACUAAGUUUAGAUCUACUUGUAGAUCAAAAGAGAGCGAGGGAUUGGGGGAGAAAGAAGGGGGGAGAGAGAGAGAGAAAGAGAAAGAGAGAAAGAGAAAAAGAGAAAGAGAAAGAGAGAAAGAGAGAGAGAGAGAUGCACUAGGUAGUCUAACUUAACUCACCAUGGAAACUCAUCCAGAAACCACGUAGUAGCAAAGCAUAUUGUUAUCUAGAGGUUUUUUCUCUUUGUAUUGAGGAAAUACCAACAAGAGAGAGAGUCAGAAAGAGGGAGCUAUUUUAAAAAUGAGAUAAUGUAAGUACUUGGGAUUCAGAUUUUUUUCAAAAAUGUCUACAGGUACAAUAAGACACCAAUAAUAUAUGUGUCCUGGCCCACUAAAUAGAUUGCUUUUAGAAGAAUGUUUGGAUAGCAUAACUUAGUAUGAUUUCCAAUGGAAAAUUAUUAGAAUAUUUAGUGGUUUAAAGUAUGGUCUUCAGUCAAUUUAAAUAAUAACUUUUCUGAUUCAUAUUAGAAGCUCCUAUUUCAACAUGAAAUAAUAAUUUUAAUGCUUUGAUAUUUUAGUUUCAAAUAUAUACAACAAAUACAUAAAUGCAAAGGCAAGGCUUAGGGAAGCCGCCAAAUGAAAGUAAACUCUCACUGAUUCCUACCUCAGAAGCAGCGAGGGAUACAUUCUUUUGACCAUAGGCCUUACUUAGAAACCCAAUGGUGUAACAUAGAAAGGGCAAGGAACAAGAAAAUAUGAGCCUCCCAAAAAGCCUCUGGCUCCUUUGUACCUUAAUUUCACCUUCCUUUUUUCAGCAUUAAUUAAAAGAGCUACUGAUUUUCAGGUUCUAAUGGAAAAUGCACAUUUAUAUUUUUCCCUCCCUCAUGAGACAGAUGCCAUAAGAAAAAUGUAGGGCCACUCCUGCAGCUCUAAUCCUAAAAAGGUCUAAGCUAAGCCCUGUUUUUGUUUUUUUGACCUUGGGUUAAAAACUCUUUAACUUCUUUUUAUUUAACAUAAUCUUUUUUGAACUCAACA